GUAGUGGGAGGAUACCUCCAGAGAGGCUGCUGCUCAUUGAGCUGCACUCACAUGAGGAUACAGACUUUGUGAAGAAGGAAUUGGCAACACUGAAACCUCCAGAACAAAGGCUGUCACUAAGGUCCCGCUGCCUUGAUGGAUUAUACACUUGACCUCAGUGUGACAACAGUGACCGACUACUACUACCCUGAUAUCUUCUCAAGCCCCUGUGAUGCGGAACUUAUUCAGACAAAUGGCAAGUUGCUCCUUGCUGUCUUUUAUUGCCUCCUGUUUGUAUUCAGUCUUCUGGGAAACAGCCUGGUCAUCCUGGUCCUUGUGGUCUGCAAGAAGCUGAGGAGCAUCACAGAUGUAUACCUCUUGAACCUGGCCCUGUCUGACCUGCUUUUUGUCUUCUCCUUCCCCUUUCAGACCUACUAUCUGCUGGACCAGUGGGUGUUUGGGACUGUAAUGUGCAAAGUGGUGUCUGGCUUUUAUUACAUUGGCUUCUACAGCAGCAUGUUUUUCAUCACCCUCAUGAGUGUGGACAGGUACCUGGCUGUUGUCCAUGCCGUGUAUGCCCUAAAGGUGAGGACGAUCAGGAUGGGCACAACGCUGUGCCUGGCAGUAUGGCUAACCGCCAUUAUGGCUACCAUCCCAUUGCUAGUGUUUUACCAAGUGGCCUCUGAAGAUGGUGUUCUACAGUGUUAUUCAUUUUACAAUCAACAGACUUUGAAGUGGAAGAUCUUCACCAACUUCAAAAUGAACAUUUUAGGCUUGUUGAUCCCAUUCACCAUCUUUAUGUUCUGCUACAUUAAAAUCCUGCACCAGCUGAAGAGGUGUCAAAACCACAACAAGACCAAGGCCAUCAGGUUGGUGCUCAUUGUGGUCAUUGCAUCUUUACUUUUCUGGGUCCCAUUCAACGUGGUUCUUUUCCUCACUUCCUUGCACAGUAUGCACAUCUUGGAUGGAUGUAGCAUAAGCCAACAGCUGACUUAUGCCACCCAUGUCACAGAAAUCAUUUCCUUUACUCACUGCUGUGUGAACCCUGUUAUCUAUGCUUUUGUUGGGGAGAAGUUCAAGAAACACCUCUCAGAAAUAUUUCAGAAAAGUUGCAGCCAAAUCUUCAACUACCUAGGAAGACAAAUGCCUAGGGAGAGCUGUGAAAAGUCAUCAUCCUGCCAGCAGCACUCCUCCCGUUCCUCCAGCGUAGACUACAUUUUGUGAGGAUCAAUGAAGACUAAAUAUAAAAAACAUUUUCUUGAAUGGCAUGCUAGUAGCAGUGAGCAAAGGUGUGGGUGUGAAAGGUUUCCAAAAAAAGUUCAGCAUGAAGGAUGCCAUAUAUGUUGUUGCCAACACUUGGAACACAAUGACUAAAGACAUAGUUGUGCAUGCCUGGCACAACAUCAAGCCUGUGAUUGUGUUUAUUGAUGAUGUUGAACAAGUGGUAACUUUAAAGGAUUCUGUAUGCCAAGUGAAAAAAAAAGAUGUCUGACCUCCUUACAUAU